GCGCGCUCCGCUCGGCAGCCUGUGGGACGCGACCGCGGCGCUAGUCUCGUUCCUUUGUGCUGCGGCGGCGGCUUCUCGAGUCCUCCCCGACGCGUCCUCUAGGCCAGCGAGCCCCGCGCUCUCCGGUGACGGACCAUGUCGGCGGCGGGAGCGGGCGCGGGCGUAGAGGCGGGCUUCUCCAGCGAGGAGCUGCUCUCGCUCCGUUUCCCGCUGCACCGCGCCUGCCGCGACGGGGACCUGGCCACGCUCUGCUCGCUGCUGCAGCAGACACCCCACGCCCACCUGGCCUCUGAGGACUCCUUCUAUGGCUGGACGCCCGUGCACUGGGCCGCGCAUUUCGGCAAGUUGGAGUGCUUAGUGCAGUUGGUGAGAGCGGGAGCCACACUCAACGUCUCCACCACACGGUACGCGCAGACGCCAGCCCACAUUGCAGCCUUUGGGGGACAUCCUCAGUGCCUGGUCUGGCUGAUUCAAGCAGGAGCCAACAUUAACAAACCGGAUUGUGAGGGUGAAACUCCCAUUCACAAGGCAGCUCGCUCUGGGAGCCUAGAAUGCAUCAGUGCCCUUGUGGCGAAUGGGGCUCACGUCGACCUGAGAAAUGCCAGUGGCCUGACAGCAGCAGACAUUGCACAAACCCAGGGUUUCCAAGAGUGUGCCCAGUUUCUCUUGAACCUCCAGAAUUGUCAUCUGAACCAUUUCUAUAACAAUGGCAUCUUAAAUGGGGGUCAUCAGAAUGUAUUUCCUAAUCAUAUUAGUGUGGGAACAAAUCGAAAGAGAUGCUUGGAAGACUCAGAAGACUUUGGAGUAAAGAAAGCUAGAACUGAAGCUCAAAGCUUGGAUUCUGCCGUGCCACUCACGAAUGGCGACACAGAAGACGAUGCUGACAAAAUGCACGUUGAUAGGGAGUUUGCUGUUGUAACAGGUGGGAGUGGACAGUUUCCUGUUAGCUGCAACAACAAUCCAAUGGUUGAAGACACCAAACAGCAGGAGAGUGGUUCUGUUGGACCAAAAGAAAUAGAAAUAUAUACUGUGUCAGCAAUGCAGACCCCCUGUCGUUGCAGGAAUCAAUAUGAAAAACAGUAGCUCCGUAUCGAAUACAUUGACAAAUGGAUGUGUCAUCAAUGGACAUUUGGACUUCCCCUCCACGACCCCGCUCAGUGGGAUGGAAAGCAGGAAUGGCCAGUGCUUGACAGGAACUAACGGAAUUAGCAGUGGAUUAGCCCCAGGACAGCCGUUUCCGAGUAGCCAGGGUUCUCUCUGCAUUAGUGGGACUGAGGAGCCAGAGAAGACCCUGAGAGCUAACCCUGAGUUGUGCGGUUCUCUGCACCUGAACGGGAGUCCAAGUAGCUGCAUAGCCAGUAGGCCUUCCUGGGUGGAAGACAUUGGGGAUAACCUGUACUAUGGACACUACCACGGGUUUGGGGACACUGCUGAAAGCAUCCCAGAACUGAACAGUGUGGUCGAGCAUUCCAAGUCCGUGAAGGUGCAGGAGCGGUACGACAGUGCCGUGCUGGGCACCAUGCACCUGCACCACGGCUCCUAGAGACGCUGACCUGGCUCUCGGAAACGCAGGAGUCCUUCCUGGUAGCCAGCUCAGAAUACCCAUGUAGCAGCAACUUGAACGAAUGUCACAACUUGUACGUUUUUUAUAUACUUCAACUUUCUGAAAAAGUAAACUUCGACAAGUUCCCAGCAACUGCUUGUUUGUGCAUGAGUAGGGCUUACUAAGUGCAUAGAUGUUUCUACAGUGAGGUGUCCUUUUUAUAAGGUGCACUUUUGGAGUUUUUCUGAUGCCAAUCUCAACAUUGUCUUUUUAAUACUGUCACCAGAUAUUGCCAUUUUUCUUUUUGUUAAAAGAUUAUAUGAUCAAGAUAAAUUGGGGUGGUAAAUCAGGUGCCUGGUAAUUUAUCUCUUUGCACAUGGGCAUCAUUUUAAAAAGCUUGCUUCCACUCUUUUCUGUAGAAUUUGACGGAACACAGCUAUUUCCCUAUGCAAGGUACAGCCUUACAAAGAUUUCUGCAGUGAUUUGUGUGAAGAAGAGAACGUUUGUCUUUUUCAAUGAAGCUUUGCAGAUCACCAUGUGGUUGAAGGUUUUAGUUGUGGACACAGUGGUCCCUCCUUAAUGAUGAAGAUCACUGCCUUGGGCUUCAUGGAAAACAGGCCCAGCCUGGGGCUGCGUUUGGAUUUAUUGUUUUUAUUCCACACUUCCUACUUGGUCUCUGGAAGUUUUACCACAUGUAACAGAUUCCUUUAUAUGUAGUGGAAAUCACUAUUUGUAGAAACUGUCAGGUCAAAAUAUUUAACUGACUGUUGACAUGUAUUUUCUUUUUUCCUUGUUUUUGUUUUUUGGGGUUUUCUGCUUUAAGAUAUAUACCACUAUGUAUAUCCAGUUAACUGAGAGAAUUUUGACUCUCUUAAUAAAACUGCAUUAAGUUUUUGAUUUUGUAGAAAUUAGCUUUUGUCUAGGCAACUAGUGGUUAUACUCUGCAAAUAUUGUAAUGAAUUUUUACUUUUUUGAUUUUUGUAAUAAAAAUUGGUGCAGAUAAAAUGUCAAAUGAACAAACCAGUGUUCUAAGAGUGUUACUAACAUUUUGUUCUAAAACUGUCCUUCACAAAUUGAAUAAAAAACUCUCACACUCA